UCAACCCAGGAGAAAUUUCAUCUCAAAAAUAACAAAUGGAUUAAAAAUGAAUAUGAACCACAAGGAACCUUCACCCCCAGGUGAACAUUUUAAUAGGUUUCCUGACGAAUGAAGUGGAAGUUGGCUCACGGUGUGCUCAGCCUCUGAAGCAACUGGAUUCAGGCAGAGGCAGGUGAGACUUCCCUCGAGCACCUCCUGCCUCCUGCCCUGCCCAGAGGCUCCGACUGAGGAUGUGGCACCUCGUUCCUUAGGCAGCUUUUCCUGGGCUCCUGUGAAGACCCUGCAGUGGAGAGAAAGCUGGUUCACCAGGAAUCCGGGGAGCCCCACAGACCCUGCAUUGGAGAGAAAGCUGGUUCACCAGGAAUCCGGGGAGCCCCGCAGACCCUGCACUGGAGAGAAAGCUGGUUCACCAGGAAUCCGGGGAGCCCCGCAGACCCUGCAUUGGAGAGAAAGCUGGUUCACCAGGAAUCCGGGGAGCCCCGCAGACCCUGCAUUGGAGAGAAAGCUGGUUCACCAGGAAUCCGGGGAGCCCCGCAGACCCUGCAGUGAGCUCAGCUCUGACCCCACGUGAGCAAUUCUCCCCUCUGCACGAAGCUCGCUGUUGGCUCGGCCCAUGGACAGAGGCAAGCACCCCGGGGCCAGCCCCUGUGCCAGCGAGCUCCGUGCCCGGGCGAGGCAUGCCUGCCGGGGGAAGUGAGUCAUCGCCCGUCGCCCAAGCCAGUGGCUGCACAAGGCAGGGGCAGGAAGAGGCAGAAGCCGCUUGGUAGCUGACAACAGAACACGUUUACGGGCCUGGGGACUGCUCCUGGGCGUUCCAGAAGCUUUCCUAGGAGGGAUACUCUGCCUGGGCUGGAGGCCUCGAAGCAGCAGGGAGGGCAGAGCCAGCCACCCUGGGCACACCCGACUGGAGGGGCUGCCUCCACCAGCCCCAGGCACUUUCCUCUCACCCAAUGGCAAGAAUUUCCAUUCCAAUAUCAGUAUUCAAUACUCAGUGCUGACUAAAUAAUUACUAAAAUUGAGUACUGGGGUCUCGACAUGAGAAAAGAAAGUCAGGCCAAUGCCUGGGAACAAGGAUGGAGAGUUUUGUGACAGUAUCUUGGAGACAUGAAGGCUCACUCUGCUUCCUGCUCAGACAAGCCUGGGGACCCUUGGGUGUGUCAUGUUCCCUGCAGAGCCGACACUCCGUUGUCAUGUGUGUUAGGAAGAGAGUCACCAGGGCCGUCCCGCCUACUUUGUCUCCAGCACCAGGUCUGACCCUUGUGCGUGGUCUCAGAAGGGCACAGGUGCUGACGAUGGAAAAACAGCUUGUUGUGAAAGUGACACAGAGCUCACAGUUAUCUCCUGAAACUCUUGGAAGGGAAACUAUGAGAACCAUAAAUGUUCAUCUGCAUGUGGUUAUUGGGCCACAAGAAAUAGCAGCCCGACCCUCAGUUUGGUCCAGGAACAAAGUUUGGCAAGCCAGCCAGGAGAGACCAGGAUGGUGCUGUGGUCAGCGGCUUGCGACGAGACACUCUUCAGGAGGAUCUCAGCAGCUACUGGUGAGAUUUUCCCGGGGACCCUCCGGAGGACUGUCUGGUGUGCAACAUUUCAUGUCCCUUUCACUACUGGGGAAGAACGGAGAUCAGGAGCAGAUGCUCUCCAAGGGCACCUUCUGGGGAUAAUGGCAGGGGCAGUGUCUUCCUCACCGCUGGGGCUUCAUGCUUCCUGUGUCUGCAGUCUACUUCUUCAAACAAACAGAAGUUUUAUAGAAUCCAUUUCACCCGUGCCCUAGUGCGUUCCAAGGACUCCAGAAAAACACCUUGCCCCACCUGUUCUCAUAAGAGGACUGCUCCCCUGGGAAUCAACACUGUGAAAAUGGCCACAUUGCCCAAAGCAGUCCACAGAUUUGAUGCAAUCCCUACCAAAACAACAACAUCGUUUUCACAGAAUUAAGAAAAACAAUCCUAAAAUUCACAUGUAACAAAAAAAGAGCCCGAAUAACUAAGGCAGUCCUAAGAAAAAUGCUGAAGGCAUCUCGCUACCUGAUCUCAAGUCAUACUAUAAGGCUAUUGUAACCCAAACAGCAUGGUAUUAGUAUGAAAACAGGCACAUAGAUCAGUGGAACAGAAUAGAGAACCCAGAGAUAACGCAGCAUAUCUACAGCCAACUGAUCUUUGACAAAGUCAACAAAAAUAUGCACUGAGGAAAGGACUCCCUUUUCGAUAAAUAGUGCUGGGAAAAUCGGAUUGUCAUGAGCAGAAGAAUUUAACUGCAUCCCUAUCUCUCCCCAUAUCAAAAAUCAACUCAAGAUGGAUUAAAGAUUUGAAUCUUAAGACCUGAAACUAUUAAAAUACUAGAAGAAACCCUAGAGGAAACUUUUCUGGACAUUGGUCUAGGCAAACAAUUCAUGACAAAGACCUCAAAAGUAAAUGCAACAAAAACAAAAAUAGACAAAUGGGACUUAAUUAAACUAAAACUCUUCUGCACAUCAAAAGAAACAAUUAACAGAGUGUACAGACAACCUGCAGAAUGGGAGAAAAUAUUUGCAAACUAUGCACCCAACAGGGGACGAAUAUCUAGAAUUUACUAGGAACUGAAACAACUCAACAGCAACAACAACAAAAACUAACUCCAGUAAAAACUGGGCAAAGGACUUGACAAGAUAUUUUUCAAAAGAAGACAUACAAAAGGCCAGCAAACAUGAAAAAAUGCUCAAAUCACUACUCACCAGAGAAAUGCAAAUUAAAACCUCAAUGAGAUACCAUCUUACAUCCGUCAGAAUGGCUAUUAUUAUAAAGACAAAAAACAACAGAUGCUGGCAAGGAGGUGGAGAAAAGGGAACUCACACAUUAUUGGUGGAAAUGGAAAUGAGUACAACCUCUAUGGAAAACAGUAUGGAGAUUUCUCAAAGAACUAAUGAUAGACCAAGCACUGAUGCCAGCAGUUCCACCACUGGGUAUCUAUUUACCCAAAGGAAAAUAAAUUAUUGUAUCAAAAUGAUACCGGCACUUGUAAAUUUUUUGCAGCACUAUUCACAAUAGCAAAGAUACGGAAUGAACCUAUGUGUCUAUCAACAGAUGAUUGGAUAAAGAAAAUGUGAUGUAUAUCCACACACACAAUUGUAUCACAUUACAAUGUGAUAAAAUUCCAUAUAUGCAAUGGAAUACUAUUUGGUCAUAAAAAAGAAUAACAUUAUGUCUUAAGCAGCAACAUGGAUGGAACUGGAGGCCAUUAUCUUAAGUGAAAUAACACAGAAACAGAAAGUAAAAUACUGAGUGUUCUCAUUUAUAAGUGGGAGGUAAAUAAUGUGUAAAUGUGAGAAUGUGGGAUGAUAGACAUUGGAGACGUAGAAGGAUGGGAGGGAGUGAGGGAUGAGAAAUUAUCCAAUGGGUGCAACGUACAUUAUUCGGGUGAUGGAUACAAUAAAAUACCAAACUUCGCUACUGUACAAUAUAUCCAUGUAACAAAACUGCAGCUGUACUCCCUAAAUUUUUUAAAAUACAUAUAAAUGCUUGACAUUAUUAUACAUGUAAAUGGAAUAGAAAUAGAAACAGAAAAUAAAUGCUUCAAGUGUUUUACA